CGAGCCCUUGGCGUUCAGUUCGCGGUGUCAGCCUCCGCCUCCGAGCCUCAGUUGUCUUCUCUGUGAGGUGGGAAUGCCGGUGAAUCCUGCCGCUGGCGUGGAUGAGAAGUGAAUGCGUGCUCGGAGCUGCGAGUGACAGCGGGCAGGAGGCGCCCAGGGACACUUGGUUUCUCCAGGGCUGGAAGGCUUCUAGAAGGUUCCUCAUCAAGGGAAGUGUGGCUGGGGGCGCCGUCUACCUGGUGUACGACCAGGAGCUGCUGGGGCCCAGCGACAAGAGCCAGGCAGCCCUACAGAAGGCUGGGGAGGUGGUCCCCCCCGCCAUGUACCAGUUCAGCCAGUACGUGUGUCAGCAGACAGGCCUGCAGAUACCCCAGCUCCCAGCCCCUCCAAAGAUUUACUUUCCCAUCCGUGACUCCUGGAAUGCAGGGAUCUAAAAGGGAAAGGAGGCCGAGCACAGUGGCUCACGCCUGUAAUCCCAGCACUUUGGGAGGCUGAGGUGGGCGGAUCAUCUGAAGUCAGGAGUUCGAGACCAGCCUGGGCAACAUGGUGAAACCCCAUCUCUACUAAAAAUACAAAAAUUAACCGUGCGUGGUGGUGCACACCUGUAAUCCCAGCUGCUGCUUGAGAGGCUGAAGCAGGAGAAUUGCUUGAACCCAGGAGGCAGAGGUUGCAGUGAGCCGAGGUUGCACCACUGCACUCCAGCCUGGGCGACAGGGCGAGACUCCAUCUCAAAAAAAUAAAAUACAAAAAUUAGCCUGG